AGUUUUCAGGCGGAUUGCCUCAGAUCACACUAUCUCCACUUGCCCAGCCCUGUGGAAGAUUAGCGGCCAUGUAUUCCAAUGUGAUAGGAACUGUAACCUCUGGAAAAAGCGUGGGGAAUUGAGCACAUAAUACUCCAAAUAACCAUCAGAUGAUUCUAAUUCCAACAUGACCACGUCCAGGCAACUGAACUGUCCCCUGGCAAGAAGUCUAGGACUGAACCUGUCCCGGGCCCCUGUACUUGGUUCAAAGGAUUUAGCCUUUCUCUUGGCCACACCAGGAAGGUUUAUCUUUUGUCCUUGCUGCUCAUUGGCUUCUGGGACUGCGUGACCUGUCACGGGAGCCCUGUGGACAUCUGCACAGCCAAGCCGCGGGACAUUCCCAUGAAUCCCAUGUGCAUUUACCGCUCCCCGGAGAAGAAGGCAACUGAGGAUGAGGGCUCAGAACAGAAGAUCCCGGAGGCCACCAACCGGCGUGUCUGGGAACUGUCCAAGGCCAAUUCCCGCUUUGCUACCACUUUCUAUCAGCACCUGGCAGAUUCCAAGAAUGACAAUGAUAACAUUUUCCUGUCACCCCUGAGUAUCUCCACGGCUUUUGCUAUGACCAAGCUGGGUGCCUGUAAUGACACCCUCCAGCAACUGAUGGAGGUAUUUAAGUUUGACACCAUAUCUGAGAAAACAUCUGAUCAGAUCCACUUCUUCUUUGCCAAACUGAACUGCCGACUCUAUCGAAAAGCCAACAAAUCCUCCAAGUUAGUAUCAGCCAAUCGCCUUUUUGGAGACAAAUCCCUUACCUUCAAUGAGACCUACCAGGACAUCAGUGAGUUGGUAUAUGGAGCCAAGCUCCAGCCCCUGGACUUCAAGGAAAAUGCAGAGCAAUCCAGAGCGGCCAUCAACAAAUGGGUGUCCAAUAAGACCGAAGGCCGAAUCACCGAUGUCAUUCCCUCGGAAGCCAUCAAUGAGCUCACUGUUCUGGUGCUGGUUAACACCAUUUACUUCAAGGGCCUGUGGAAGUCAAAGUUCAGCCCUGAGAACACAAGGAAGGAACUGUUCUACAAGGCUGAUGGAGAGUCGUGUUCAGCAUCUAUGAUGUACCAGGAAGGCAAGUUCCGUUAUCGGCGCGUGGCUGAAGGCACCCAGGUGCUUGAGUUGCCCUUCAAAGGUGAUGACAUCACCAUGGUCCUCAUCUUGCCCAAGCCUGAGAAGAGCCUGGCCAAGGUAGAGAAGGAACUCACCCCAGAGGUGCUGCAAGAGUGGCUGGAUGAAUUGGAGGAGAUGAUGCUGGUGGUCCACAUGCCCCGCUUCCGCAUUGAGGACGGCUUCAGUUUGAAGGAGCAGCUGCAAGACAUGGGCCUUGUCGAUCUGUUCAGCCCUGAAAAGUCCAAACUCCCAGGUAUUGUUGCAGAAGGCCGAGAUGACCUCUAUGUCUCAGAUGCAUUCCAUAAGGCAUUUCUUGAGGUAAAUGAAGAAGGCAGUGAAGCAGCUGCAAGUACCGCUGUUGUGAUUGCUGGCCGUUCGCUAAACCCCAACAGGGUGACUUUCAAGGCCAACAGGCCUUUCCUGGUUUUUAUAAGAGAAGUUCCUCUGAACACUAUUAUCUUCAUGGGCAGAGUAGCCAACCCUUGUGUUAAGUAAAAUGUUCUUAUUCUUUGCACCUCUUCCUAUUUUUGGUUUGUGAACAGAAGUAAAAAUAAAUACAAACUACUUCCAUCUCACAUUAUAAA